CCUUUAGCCCCGCCCGCCUCCGUAGCUGCCUGAAGUAGUGCAGGGUCAGCCCGCAAGUUGCAGGUCAUGGCGCUGGCUGCUCGACUGUGGCGCCUUCUGCCUUUCCGACGUGGAGCCGCCCCGGGGUCUCGUCUCCCUGCGGGGACUUCGGGCAGCCGCGGGCAUUGCGGCCCCUGUCGAUUCCGCGGCUUCGAGGUACCCCCGUGGUCCUGGCUCCCGCUCCUCACUUCCUACUCAGUAAUGGGAAACCCAGGAACUUUCAAAAGAGGCCUUUUACUCUCAGCUUUGUCGUAUUUGGGUUUUGAAACUUACCAGGUUAUCUCUCAGGCUGCUGUGGUUCAUGCCACAGCCAAAGUUGAAGAAAUACUUGAACAAGCAGACUACCUGUAUGAAAGCGGAGAAACAGAAAAACUUUAUCAGUUGCUAACCCAAUACAAGGAAAGUGAAGAUGCAGAGUUACUGUGGCGUUUGGCACGGGCAUCACGUGAUGUAGCUCAGCUUAGCAGAACCUCAGAAGAGGAGAAAAAGCUAUUGGUGUAUGAAGCCCUAGAGUAUGCAAAAAGAGCACUAGAAAAAAAUGAAUCAAGUUUUGCAUCUCAUAAGUGGUAUGCAAUCUGCCUUAGUGAUGUUGGAGAUUAUGAAGGCAUCAAGGCUAAAAUUGCAAAUGCAUAUAUCAUCAAGGAGCAUUUUGAGAAAGCAAUUGAACUGAACCCUAAAGAUGCUACUUCAAUUCACCUUAUGGGUAUUUGGUGCUAUACAUUUGCCGAAAUGCCUUGGUAUCAAAGAAGAAUUGCUAAAAUGCUGUUUGCAACUCCUCCUAGUUCCACCUAUGAGAAGGCCUUAGGCUACUUUCACAGGGCAGAACAAGUGGAUCCAAACUUCUACAGCAAAAACUUACUUCUUUUAGGAAAGACAUACUUGAAACUACACAACAAAAAGCUUGCUGCUUUCUGGCUAAUGAAAGCCAAGGACUAUCCAGCACACACAGAGGAGGAUAAACAGAUACAGACAGAAGCUGCUCAGUUGCUUACAAGUUUCAGUGAGAAGAAUUGAGAACUUUUCAGAGAAGAUUUAUGAAAUAGCUAAUAAACAUUGCCUUUUCUUUUAAUUCUAAACUUAAUAUAUGAACUAUAACUGUUCUACGGCUUUUUAAAUGUUGUGACCAUUUAACCGUGUAAAUAUAAAAUAUUCUAGGCUUCUUCACAAAUAAUAGGGUAAAAUAAAUAAUCGCCAUAAGAGUGGUAGAAAUAAAUCUCCAUGGCUCAGGCAAAGAGAUUAUUUUGCAUCCUGGAUACCAGCAAUGCAAAAUGGUAUGAGAUUUCUAAGGAUUGAUCACAUUGGGAUGGGAGAUCAAGCAAAGAAAUAUUUGUAGAGGAGGGGAAAUGGAUCUAUAGGGGAUAUACAGGGGGAUGGAUUUUCAAAUUGGAUUGAUUCUAAGUUGAAAUCUUGAAGAGAAGGUGUGGUGACAGUGGUUAGGAUGUUGUGGGUUCCUGACAUAAAGUAGUUAAAUGAUAUAUCUUGGAGCUAACCUGUGUAAGUAAAGAACUAAGUAAGGAGAUGACUAAAAAUGGAGUAGUUUCCUUUUUUAUUUUUUUGAGACAGAGUCUCACUUUGUUUCCCAGGCUGGUGUGCAGUGGCACAAUCUCGGCCCACUGCAGCCUCCGCCUCCCGGGUUCAAGUGAUUCUCCUGCCUUAGCCUCCUGAGUGGCUGGGAUUACAGGGUUGUACCACCACACUCGGCUAACUUUUGUAUUUUUGGUAGAGAUGGGGUUUUGCCAUGUUGGCUAGGCUGGUCUCAAACUCCUGGCCUCAAGUGAUCUGCCCGCCUUGGCCUCCCAAAUUGCUGGGAUUACAGGCGUGAGCCACCGCACCUGGCCAGUUUACUUUAAAUGUGGUGUAGUCUCAUGGUAAACUGAAUUUGUCAUCAGAUGCAAAGUUCUAUUCCCUAAUGGAAUGGAAGGAACACAAAACUUAAGAGUGAAAUGGAAUACUAAGAUGUUUUUAAAUAGGCAGGACUAUGCUACUCACUUGAGGCUGGAGUGCCACCACUGCAAAAUCUUUUUAAGUUUUGUAAAAAGGAGCAUCUUGAAUCCACUUAGAUAAAGACAGACUGUGUGUGUAGGUGGAUUUUUCCCAAAGGAUUUGGGAAUUGUAAUGUUACAAUGAACUGUAUGGAUAUGUUUGUCAUGUACAUUUUCAAACAAAAAGGAAAACUGAAAGUAGUGAUCUUUGUAUACCCAUCUCUUAGAUUCAGUGAUUUUGCUAUAUAGGUUGUGUAUCCCUUAUCUGAAAUACUUGGGACUAGUAGAAGCAUCUUGGAUUUGGGAUGUUUUUCCAAAUUUUGGAAUACCUGCAUACACACAAUAAGAUAUCUUGGAGAUGGGACCCAAGUUUAAACACAAAUUCACUUGUUUCAUAUAUACCUUAUGCACAUAGCUUGAAGGUAACUUUAUAUAACAUUAUUUUUAAUAAUUUUGUGCAUUGAGACCAAGUUUGCAUACCUUGAACCAUCAGAAAGCAAAGGUGUCAUUAUCUCAGCCACUCAUGUGGGUAAUUUGUGGUUGGUUGAUGUCACCAUCAUUCCUGACUGAAUGUAUAUGCUACCAAUAAGCAGUUAUUUUCUUAUACUUAUUCAUGCAUAAGUACUUAACAGUAAAAAAUAUGACAUAACUCGCACAGGAACAAGGAUGGCAAAAAAAAAAAUAUGACACACCACUGAUACAGUGAAAAAAUAAUGUGGUCAGGGUAGCUAGGCAACAGUAGCAUCACCAGAAACCUGUAUCAGCUGUUAAACGGCAACAACAAUGGCAGGCUUUCAGUUUCCCACUUAAUGAUGCUGUAUUUUAAAAGGUUAUUGUAUACUGUAAUUUUAUUUUUGUAGGUGAAGAGAAACAGAAGCAGCUGAAGGGCCAGGAAGUGGGUCUUUCUAGGGAUGUGGCAUUCUGCUGGAUGGCUUUUUAAAAUGGGUUUUUUCCUUUAGGGAGACCGAAUAAACUGUGUUGUGCACCUGCA